CUUCCCCUUCUCCCAUCCCUCUCUCGGCCACAGCGUCUUGUUAGUCCUCUCCCUGUACUCCGCAAUAUUUUCUUUCUUUCUCCCUCCUCUCCUCCAUUUGUUGUUUGAUGUUUCCCACUCUUUGAGGAAGGAUGGUUGAUUUGGAGAGCGAAGUGCCCCCUCUGCCUCCCAGGUACAGGUUUCGAGAUUUGCUGCUAGGGGACCAAGGAUGGCAAAACGACGACAGGGUACAAGUUGAAUUCUAUAUGAAUGAAAAUACAUUUAAAGAAAGACUAAAAUUAUUUUUCAUAAAAAACCAGAGAUCAAGUCUAAGGAUACGCCUGUUCAAUUUUUCUCUCAAAUUACUAAGCUGCUUAUUAUACAUAAUCCGAGUACUACUAGAAAACCCUUCACAAGGAAAUGAAUGGUCUCAUAUCUUUUGGGUGAACAGAAGUCUACCUUUGUGGGGCUUACAGGUUUCAGUGGCAUUGAUAAGUCUGUUUGAAACAAUAUUACUUGGUUAUCUUAGUUAUAAGGGAAACAUCUGGGAACAGAUUUUACGAAUACCCUUCAUCUUGGAAAUAAUUAAUGCAGUUCCCUUCAUUAUCUCAAUAUUCUGGCCUUCCUUAAGGAAUCUAUUUGUCCCAGUCUUUCUGAACUGUUGGCUUGCCAAACAUGCCUUGGAAAAUAUGAUUAAUGAUCUACACAGAGCCAUUCAGCGUACACAGUCUGCAAUGUUUAAUCAAGUUUUGAUUUUAAUAUCUACAUUACUAUGCCUUAUCUUCACCUGCAUUUGUGGGAUCCAACAUCUGGAACGAAUAGGAAAGAAGCUGAAUCUCUUUGACUCCCUUUAUUUCUGCAUUGUGACGUUUUCUACUGUGGGCUUCGGGGAUGUCACUCCUGAAACAUGGUCCUCCAAGCUUUUUGUAGUUGCUAUGAUUUGUGUUGCUCUUGUGGUUCUACCCAUACAGUUUGAACAGCUGGCUUAUUUGUGGAUGGAGAGACAAAAGUCAGGAGGAAACUAUAGUCGACAUAGAGCUCAAACUGAAAAGCAUGUCGUCCUGUGUGUCAGCUCACUGAAGAUUGAUUUACUUAUGGAUUUUUUAAAUGAAUUCUAUGCUCAUCCUAGGCUCCAGGAUUAUUAUGUGGUGAUUUUGUGUCCUACUGAAAUGGAUGUACAGGUUCGAAGGGUACUGCAGAUUCCAAUGUGGUCCCAACGAGUUAUCUACCUUCAAGGUUCAGCCCUUAAAGAUCAAGACCUAUUGAGAGCAAAGAUGGAUGACGCUGAGGCCUGUUUUAUUCUCAGUAGCCGUUGUGAAGUGGAUAGGACAUCAUCUGAUCACCAAACAAUUUUGAGAGCAUGGGCUGUGAAAGAUUUUGCUCCAAAUUGUCCUUUGUAUGUCCAGAUAUUAAAGCCUGAAAAUAAAUUUCACAUCAAAUUUGCUGAUCAUGUUGUUUGUGAAGAAGAGUUUAAAUACGCCAUGUUAGCUUUAAACUGUAUAUGCCCAGCAACAUCUACACUUAUUACACUACUGGUUCAUACCUCUAGAGGGCAAGAAGGCCAGCAAUCGCCAGAACAAUGGCAGAAGAUGUACGGUAGAUGCUCCGGGAAUGAAGUCUACCACAUUGUUUUGGAAGAAAGUACAUUUUUUGCUGAAUAUGAAGGAAAGAGUUUUACAUAUGCCUCUUUCCAUGCACACAAAAAGUUUGGCGUCUGCUUGAUUGGUGUUAGGAGGGAGGAUAAUAAAAACAUUUUGCUGAAUCCAGGUCCUCGAUACAUUAUGAAUUCUACAGACAUAUGCUUUUAUAUUAAUAUUACCAAAGAAGAGAAUUCAGCAUUUAAAAACCAAGACCAGCAGAGAAAAAGCAAUGUGUCCAGGUCGUUUUAUCAUGGACCUUCCAGAUUACCUGUACAUAGCAUAAUUGCCAGCAUGGGUACUGUGGCUAUAGACUUGCAAGAUACAAGCUGUAGAUCAGCAAGUGGCCCUACCCUGUCUCUUCCUACAGAGGGAAGCAAAGAAAUAAGAAGACCUAGCAUUGCUCCUGUUUUAGAGGUUGCAGAUACAUCAUCGAUUCAAACAUGUGAUCUUCUAAGUGACCAAUCAGAAGAUGAAACUACACCAGAUGAAGAAAUGUCUUCAAACUUAGAGUAUGCUAAAGGUUACCCACCUUAUUCUCCAUAUAUAGGAAGUUCACCCACUUUUUGUCAUCUCCUUCAUGAAAAAGUACCAUUUUGCUGCUUAAGAUUAGACAAGAGUUGCCAACAUAACUACUAUGAGGAUGCAAAAGCCUAUGGAUUCAAAAAUAAACUAAUUAUAGUUGCAGCUGAAACAGCUGGAAAUGGAUUAUAUAACUUUAUUGUUCCUCUCAGGGCAUAUUAUAGACCAAAGAAAGAACUUAAUCCCAUAGUACUGCUAUUGGAUAACCCGCCAGAUAUGCAUUUUCUGGAUGCAAUCUGUUGGUUUCCAAUGGUUUACUACAUGGUGGGCUCUAUUGACAACCUAGAUGACUUACUCAGGUGUGGAGUGACUUUUGCUGCUAAUAUGGUGGUUGUGGAUAAAGAGAGCACCAUGAGUGCCGAGGAAGACUACAUGGCAGAUGCCAAAACCAUUGUGAACGUGCAGACACUCUUCAGGUUGUUUUCCAGUCUCAGUAUUAUCACAGAGCUAACUCACCCCGCCAACAUGAGAUUCAUGCAAUUCAGAGCCAAAGACUGUUACUCUCUUGCUCUUUCAAAACUGGAAAAGAUUAAAGGAAACAAAAUUUCUGCCAGAAACACAUUCCUUCUUCCAAGAAAGGCACAUGUUCAUGAUAAUAAAACAAAUGGAAAAGUAGGUAAGACCAAACAUUUAAAAGUGUCUGAAAUCUUUAAUGAUUUAAAUGUCAUUGGUAUUCUUUUAGAUACUUAUAUAAGUAUUUGUUAGGAAAAAAAUAUCAUCAGUAAAACUUCAAUUGAAUUCAGAAUUCUACUAGAAAAGAAAUAUGAUAAAUUUAACAAAAAGGAAUCAUAGUGUAUGUUUAUACUAGCAACAAUAGCAGAAACAUUUAUUGUAAAACCCAAUAACUAGACAUAGUAAAGUAAAAAAGCUUUGCAUAUUGUGACAUUACAAUUCUUCACAUUCUCAAACCUCUGUUAAAUAACCAAAGUGACAAAAUAGAGGUAUUGAGUGAACCUCGAACGUUUGUUUCUUGUUUCUGGCAUAUGAAUGUUCUAAGCAUUAAACUAUGCAAUAAAUUGUCUUUUGAUGUAGGCCGCUAACAUAAGUAGAAAAAAUUUAUUUAUUUUUCCAAUCAAAUGUCACUGACUGUGUGCCAGGCAUUGUGUUAGGCAUUGUGUAAGUAACAGAAAGCAAAAUCAUGGUCUCUGCCCUCUUGGAACAUAGGAUCUAGCUGAGAUAGAUUAUUAAUAAAUUAAAAACAUAAACAAGGUGUAAUAGGUUUCAAAAAAGCUAUGAAAGUUUUAACAGGUUAUAUUCAAGAGUAACUGCAGAAAGACAGGUUUUAAGUAAGGUGAUAAGGAAAUACCUCUUUGGGGAGGUAAUAUUUUAGCUGCAAUGAUAACACCAGCCUAGUCCAGUAAAAGCCUGGGAAGUAGCAUUAUAGGAAGGAUAAAAAAAUACAAAGUUCUUGAGGUAAUAUAUAAUUUAGCAUAUUCAAACAACUGAUAAUAAAAAUAUCUUUUUAAGUACUUACUAUAUACAGUAAUUUUAGAGGUUUUAUUAUGUUUAUUUUUUGUAAUCACAGUGGGAUGUAGAUGUCAAUAUGAAUCCCAAUUCACAGUUAUAAAACUGAGGAACAGAGAGCUUAAGUAACUUGUAAAAGAUCAUACAAUUAGUAAGCGGAAACACUUGACUGAAACUAUUGUAUGUGGUUUCAGAAUCCAAGCUCCAAACCAUUGUAUGUUGUAUUGCCUGUAUGAUCCAUAUUUUUGGCAGGUGGACCUGUCCACUGGCAUCAAAACCCAAGUCCAAAUCAACUUGUGAUCUGAUCUUCCUCCACACUUUCUAUUUUACAGAAGGUGCAAUCAUCUGCCUCAUUAUCUAGAGACCUGUGUAUCAUCCUCAUCUUCUCUCUACUUUAGUACCAAAUUCAAUCAUCAUAUCCUCUUAAAAUUGAAUGUCUAAAUGCAUUCUGAAUAAGAUCUGUUUCUGCAAAUACCACAGUAGAAUGUACAUUCGUCUUUCACUAGGAUUGCUGCAUUAACACUAUAGUUUAUCUUGCUCAAUUUUCCCAUGCCACCUCCUCAUUCACAAGCCAUUUUCCACAUUGUCAUCAAAGUGAGCAUCCUAAAAACAUAAUCGUAUCACUCCUCCUCUUAAAAACACUUUAGUUUUUCCCCAUUGCCUGUAAGAUGAAAUUCAAAAUACUUAACAUGGUUUCAAAGUAGGGUAACCAUAUGUCCUGUUAUUUCUUAGACAAUCUCAACUUAUAUCAUUAUUUUUCAGUGUAAUUCUUAACUGCAUCCCCAUUACCUUAAAACAUAUCUUGGUACUUUAAGACCUAGUCCAAACUUAUUGCUCUAGUCUCAUUUCUGACCUCUCCAUUCAACCCAUAUACUUAAACUCUAUGCUAUUGGAUUGUUUGUAGUUCCUGAAGUCUCUCAAGCGUUUUAUUUUUUUAUUUUUUAUUUAUUUAUUUUUUUUUACUUCCACUAGAGAACAUGCUGGACAUUCUGCUUAUAGCUUUCAACUUAACACUCACUCUUCCCAAAUUUCUACUCAAUUUUAGGUCUCAACUUAGACAUCACCUCUAAUUCAGCUCUCUGGCUUUUCUACUAAAAGAAUAAGCUAGGUGCCCUUCCUAAGUAUGUAUUACUGCCUAAUUAUUACAUAUAUUCACCCAAGUGUUUUUGCCUAUUUUGCUAUUGUUACCAUUCACAGCAGUGUAAGUUCUUGCAGACAAGGAAAAUAUCCCUGUUUGUUUAACUAGCUCCUGGCCCAUAUUCAACACAUAAUACUUCUAUUAACUGAUAAGAUACUGUUAGUUCUAUAUAGGAGCUCUGUAUUCCUAGCACUGAGGAUGAUUGAUGCCCUACACAAAGUACGUUCUCAACGCAUAUUUAUUAAGUGACUACUUUAAUGCACAAAUGAAUACAUUGGUGUUUGGGGACUUUAAUAGUGAAUGGAAUUAAUUUUAAUUAGCGUUGCUGUUUAAGGUGGUAUCAAUAGGAUUCAGAUGUGUGGAGAUGGGAAGAGUUCAUUUCCUAUAGGAAUAAGCACUGUAGGUUAAAAAACUGUUCUGUAUUUGAAAAAUAUAGUGUGUGAAAUGGUAAUGUAAUUGAACCAAGGAAUGUUUGUUUGUUUGUUUGUUUGUUUGUUUGUUUGUUUUGAAGAGUAAAUGUAACAUCAAAUUCUCAGGCGUUCCAGCACUUUAUUCUGGCUACUCCCUUUAAUUUGGGUCUAACAUAUCAUGGCUUGGUCUUCUCCAGGAUACUUGUUACACCUCGAGAACUAGGUUUGUCCUCAAAUUCACGGGAAAACCUAGCUGUAUCACAAUAAGAACAGCUAACUCCAGUCAUCUGCAAGCCACUCACAUGAGCUGUUCAAGUUAAGCACUCUUCACACCUAGGUUUAUAAAUUAGAGAAUAUAUUAGGAUUUCAUAGACAUAGACAAAAAUGUGGAACCGCUUUCCUAUCCUUUGCCUUACCUUCUCCCUGUAUCUCAAGUGAAGACGCUCUUAUAGUGAUAGUCAUCUCAACUAGACAGACACUAUAGAUACACGUGAGAUGGGAGGCUUCCCUUCCACGAGAACCCACACAUUUAUUACAUUAGAAACAGGAGCUUGCUUCUGUUGCCUCAAGAAGUGAAGGUUGAUUUCUUAUUUUCUGUAUCUUAUUCUGAUUUCUUAUUUUCAGCUGUAUCAGUCUUCCUAGUAAAGGGAAUUUGUCAACAAAAGAAACUAGAAUUUUUGAGGUUACCAUUUGUUAAAUAGAAGCUUAACUUACAUUCUCAAGAAACUCUUCUAAACUUAAACAAAUUUGACAUUUGCUCUCUUACCUUCAUUUAUUAAAGGAAAAAAAAAUUGCAACAGAAUUUUUAAAAAGAAACCCUCAUACACCAUAUCACCCCCCAACUCGUAAGCAUUCAAACAUACAUAAACAACGUGUGUGUGUGUGUGUGUGUGUGUGUAUGUGUGUGUGUGUGUGUGUGAUAUACAGAAGAUUAGUUGCAAACUGAUAUACCAGAUGCAAUUUAUCAGUUAGGUGGAGAAAUGAAACUAAGAUGAUGGACAGCUAGAGACUACUGGAUGUACAAAGCCUGUUUUAGUCUGUUAGGGCUACUAGAACAAAGUACUGUAGACUGGGUGGCUUAUAGACACCAGAUAUUAAUUUCUCACUGUCUGAAGGCUGGGAAUUCCACAUUCAAGGUGCUGGGAGAUUUGGUGUCUGGUGAGGGCCCAUUUCCUAGUUCAUAGAUGGUACAUGGUAGAAGGGGCAAAGAGUUUCUCUUUUUUAAAAAGGCAAUUGCAUUCAUGAGGGUUCCACCUCCAUGAACUAAUCACCUCCCAAAGGCUUCACUUCCUAAUACUAUUACCUUGGGGAUUAGGAUUUCAAUGUAUGAAUUUUGAGGGGACACAAACAUUCAGACCAUAACAGGUGCCUACCUCCCUAUUUUUUUGUUCUCACCCAUGAGAAUAUUUAAAAGCAGGUCUUCUUUACAGUGUUCAGUGUUAUGGUACAUCGUGUGACGUUAGUUUUUUUUUCACAUUUUUUUCAAUGAUUUUUAUUUGUUUCCAUUAUGAUGUCUCUUCUUGUAUGAAGAGUAAAUACAUGCUUAAUGUACAAAAAAUGUUGAUCUUUCUUCACUAUUGGGUGUUUUAACUGAGAAAAUGUGGUUAGCAAAACGAAAGGGCAGUUUAAAAAAUAUGAUUAUCAGUGAAGUAAUGACACAUUUAUAGCUAAGAACCAUAUGAUGAGAACUUUUUACGUAUGUCAACACAAUUUACUGAGGCAGAAAUGCAUAAAAUGUGGAAUGCUCACAAAUUUUUCUAUCUCAAAUUUCUGAA